CUCUUCCGGUCGCGGGACACCGGGUGUAGAGGGCGGUCGCGGCGGGCAGUGGCGGCAGAAUGUUGGCUACCAGGGUAUUUAGCCUAGUUGGCAAGCGAGCAAUUUCCACCUCUGUGUGUGUACGAGCUCAUGAAAGUGUUGUGAAGAGCGAAGACUUUUCGCUCCCAGCUUAUAUGGAUCGGCGUGACCACCCCUUGCCGGAGGUGGCCCAUGUCAAGCACCUGUCUGCCAGCCAGAAGGCAUUGAAGGAGAAGGAGAAGGCCUCCUGGAGCAGCCUCUCCAUGGAUGAGAAAGUCGAGUUGUAUCGCAUUAAGUUCAAGGAGAGCUUUGCUGAGAUGAACAGGGGCUCGAACGAGUGGAAGACGGUUGUGGGCGGUGCCAUGUUCUUCAUCGGUUUCACCGCGCUCGUUAUCAUGUGGCAGAAGCACUAUGGUCACCUUGGGCUCUGUUUGUCAGAUCCUGUUAUCCAUAGCCUUUAGAGAGGACCUUCUGCUUUUAGCUUAUUUUGUUGCUAACUUUUUACAAACAAAGGGCUAAUUUUAAAAUGUCAGUGUUGUCAGUGGUCAGAAACCGUGUGUUUGAGCGGGUGUUGAGUGGCAGGUGGCUCUGCUGACCUGGUGGCUGGUGUGUCGGGAGGAUUUAACCUGUGUGAGGGAUUGGCCUAGAAACAACCUGUUGAGAUAGUCUUGCCCCAUAACCUGUCUCACACCGUAGUGUACGGCCCCCUCCCGCAAAGCUUUGACAAAGAGUGGGUGGCCAAGCAGACCAAGAGGAUGCUGGACAUGAAGGUGAACCCCAUCCAGGGCUUAGCCUCCAAGUGGGACUACGAAAAGAACGAGUGGAAGAAGUGAGAGAUGCUGGCCUGCGCCUGCACCUGCGCCUGGCUCUGUCACCGCCAUGCAACUCCAUGCCUAUUUACUGGAAACCUGUUAUGCCAAACAGUUGUACCACUGCUAAUAAAUGACCAGUUUACCUGAAA